CCUCCACCCCAGGGCCCAGGUAGGGACCAUGUCCCCUGCCAUUGCAUUGGCCUUCCUGCCACUGGUGGUAACAUUGCUGGUGCGGUACCGGCACUACUUCCGAUUGCUGGUGCGCACGGUCUUGCUGCGAAGCCUCCGAGACUGCCUGUCAGGGCUGCGGAUCGAGGAGCGGGCCUUCAGCUACGUGCUCACCCAUGCCCUGCCCGGUGACCCUGGUCACAUCCUCACCACCCUGGACCACUGGAGCAGCCGCUGCGAGUACUUGAGCCACAUGGGGCCUGUCAAAGGUCAGAUCCUGAUGCGGCUGGUGGAGGAGAAGGCCCCUGCUUGUGUGCUGGAAUUGGGAACCUACUGUGGAUACUCUACCCUGCUUAUUGCCCGAGCCCUGCCCCCUGGGGGUCGCCUUCUUACUGUGGAGCGGGACCCACGCACGGCAGCAGUGGCUGAAAAACUCAUCCGCCUGGCCGGCUUUGAUGAGCACAUGGUGGAGCUCAUCGUGGGCAGCUCAGAGGACGUGAUCCCGUGCCUACGCACCCAGUAUCAGCUGAGUCGGGCAGACCUGGUGCUCCUGGCACACCGGCCACGAUGUUACCUGAGGGACCUGCAGCUGCUGGAGGCCCAUGCCCUACUGCCAGCAGGUGCCACCGUGCUGGCUGACCAUGUGCUCUUCCCUGGUGCACCCCGCUUCUUGCAGUAUGCUAAGAGCUGUGGCCGCUACCGCUGCCGCCUCCACCACACUGGCCUUCCAGACUUCCCUGCCAUCAAGGAUGGAAUAGCUCAGCUCACCUAUGCUGGACCAGGCUGAGGUCCAGGCCCAGGGGUACUUACUGAUGCCCACCCCCACCCCCACCCAAGCAGGGACCUCAAAAUCCCCUCCCUUUCCUGUUUGGGGCCUUGACACACGCUGGGCUCAGGGCUAGGGAGUCUCUCUUCCCACCUCUGACCUCUUUCAGCCUCUACACUGACCUCAAGUGUCAAGUUCUAUCAGGCUGCUUGGUCUCACUAGGCCCCCUCUUUCCAGAGAGAACCAUGGACUGACAGCAAGAAGCCUGAGCUCCCGACCCAGCUCUGUCACUGAUUUGCUGAGUGACUCCAAGGGAAUCCCCACCUUGCUCUGAGAUUUAAUCUUCUCUCUUAACACGAAGGAAGCUGGAUGGGAGAGCUCCAGGGGCCUCCCAGUUCUCGGCCUCAGAAAGCCUCCCAUCCUCAGCCCAUGCCAUUCUGGGUGGGAUCAGAGGAAGUGGCAAUGAGUUAGACGCCCUGCAGGAAUAGCUGGAUGCAAGCUGGGCCAGAGAAAAUGGCACAGAACCCUGGACCCAGGGCCAGGGAUGCCCUGGCCUUCCCUAACUCUGGCCCACCUAGCCAAUUAGGUGUGGCUGAUGUCCCUUGAGUGCCCUCUUCCUAAAGCCCAAAAGAAGAUGCUGGACUCCUCUGGGCCCCACCAACAAAUAGGGAAUAGACAUGGGUGGAAAAUCA